AUUAGGUCAUAUCUUCACCAGCUCUGUGGAGCAAGCAUGGUUUUCUAUUAUUUGUAAAACAAAAGUAUAGUGAUGCCUCAGUGGGGAGUGCCUUAUCCCACUCUCAGUGAUUUAACAGGGUCUGGACUUCUGUUUUUUAAAAGAUAUAUUUUAUCCUAAGCUUUUAGAAGUCAAGAUGGGGUUAGGGGAUAAAAGUCAGGGAGAGGAAUGGAGAGAGGAAGAACAGAGCCCAAGGAAGAAAGGUGACAGUCUGGACAACGCAAGAACCCCUGCGGUCUCCAGCAACCACACUCAUGUGACUUCUGCCUUCACCCUUCACAUGCAAGAGGAGGCAAGCUCAGUUGAGUUCUCACCUCCAAGAACUUGCAGUUCUCCUGGGGAGGCAGGACCGAUGCCCAUGGAACAAGGUGUGCCAGUGAGCCCCACAGAAAGGGGCAGUUUCCCGCACCAGGAUACACUUCAAAAAAGCACAAUUCAGAUUAUGCAUUCCCUGCUGAAGAUGCUCCACUGCGUCUUAUACCACUUGAGAAAAAAUUCCAGACUCCUCUCCAAUGUACUUCAGUCCCUGCCCAACUGGGCUCCAGUCAGGGUGGGGUUUUUUGUCGUUGUUGUUCUUCAAAUGCUGUCCACCACCCCAGAGGUUGUUUCUUUGCUGUUCGUGGGCCUGGAGUCCCCUUUCCCCAGGUCUUUACAUGGCUGCUCCAUCUCUCCAUAGAAGUUGCAGCUCAAGUGCCACCUUUUCAGAGAGCCCUUCCUGGACCGUUCAGUAUAAAUGAAGUUCUUUCCCCAAGUACUCCUGAUGGCAGCAACUUGUCACAGUGUCCUUCUUUGCCCUUACCAUGAGCUGGUAUUUUUCUUGUGUAUUGAUUCACUGAUUAAUUGCUUCCUUGAUUAUCCCUCAUGCUGCCCAUUAGAAUGUAGCUCCAUGGGAGCAGGGACCUUGUCUAUCUUGUCCUCCAUGGUAUCCUAGAAUUCUAAGAUGUAGGAUAGCUUAACAGAGGAGACUCUUGAAAUAUUUGUUAAAUAUGUGAUAAAAAAUAAAAGGAAGAAUCUAUGCAUGGCAG